AAUUCCGGGAAGCUCGCCUUACAACUCCGCGCGGCCUCGGCCCCCUGCGCCGCCCGCCCCACAACAAAACUCAGCGCAGCGCUCCCGGGCGCCCGGUUCAGAGCGACCUGCGGCUCAGAGCGGAGGGGAGACUGACCGGAGCGCGGAUCGGGACAGCGGCCGGGACAGCGGCGAGACGCGCGUGUGUGAGCGCGCCGGACCAAGCGGGCCCAGAAGCGGGUGAGGAACGCGGGACCAGGAGGACGGUCUGCAGCCCAGAGGGCACCUUCUGCAAACAUGUCUGUGGAUCCCCUAUCCAGCAAAGCUCUAAAGAUCAAGCGAGAGCUGAGCGAGAACACGCCGCACCUGUCGGACGAGGCGCUGAUGGGGCUGUCGGUGCGCGAGCUGAACCGGCAUCUGCGCGGGCUCUCCGCCGAGGAGGUGACACGGCUCAAGCAGCGGCGCCGCACACUCAAAAACCGUGGCUACGCCGCCAGCUGCCGCGUGAAGCGCGUGUGCCAGAAGGAGGAGCUGCAGAAGCAGAAGUCGGAGCUGGAGCGCGAGGUGGACAAGCUGGCGCGCGAGAACGCCGCCAUGCGCCUGGAGCUCGACGCGCUGCGCGGCAAGUGCGAGGCGCUGCAGGGCUUCGCGCGCUCCGUGGCCGCCGCCCGCGGGCCCGCCACGCUCGUGGCGCCGGCCAGCGUCAUCACCAUCGUCAAGUCCACCCCGGGCUCGGGGUCUGGCCCCGCCCACGGCCCGGACCCCGCCCACGGCCCGGCCUCCUGCUCCUAGUGCCCGCCCCCGCCAUGCCUCAGCCACGCCCCUCCGGCCUCAGCUCCCUCCCCAAAGUGCCUGAGCGCCGCCUCUGUGCCCAGGUCCCAUUUCUCUGCAGCACUGGCCCCUUGGUGCACACACAUUCCCUUCGUGGGCCCUGUCUUCCUCUUGCAGCCCCCCAAACUGGGACCGAAUGACCCUGGGAAGGGGAACUUGGGUAGGUUGGGGAUGGGGCAGAGGUCUGGAUCUGGGAUCGCCCUUGGCUGAAAGUUUAGCCUUUUUAGAUUGAGAGAUACAGAGCCGGCUUAGAGAACAGCUGUUGGGGGAGAAGAGGGCACCCCUCAUCUUGGAAACUGCUCUUAUUGUGCCAAUAUGCCCUCCAAACCCUCCCAGGAUUCAAAGCUAGGUUUGGCUGUCUGUGACUUACGGGACCGUCCUGCUGAGAAAUUGCACUGAAGAGAUGCCCCCACCUCUGGUUGGGCCUGGGGGUGCCUGGCCUUCCGAAACUAAAAGAGUGGGUGGGAAGACUAGUGAAACCCAGUUCACGGAUGGGGAAACAGGCCUGAGGUCACAUUUCACUUAGUGGUUGUGUUGGGACCAAAACCUGGGUGUCCUCACUGCUGCCCUGAGUCCAGCCAUGGUUUUCAGGGGGACAGUGGACAGGGACUCAGAAAUGUGGUGGGAGGGCCUCCCUGGCUUGGGAGACCGCUCUCUGCAAGGGAGGGGGAGAGAAGCAGAGGGAGAGAGAAGGUGACACGGAUGGAAGAGUGGGAAGGAGCUGGCCUGGCUCAGCCCUAGGCUGUCCCUGCAGCCAGGGUGUCCGGGGGCUGGCCAGUCAGAGAAAGGGGGCCAUGGACUGCUGUGGCAAAUAGGGAGACAAGGAGACAGACCCUGCAGUCCUACUACAGUCUGGAGUGGGGUCCUAAGAAGAAGGGUCCCACCUCAACCCCUGUCAGUGUCCACUGUGGGGUGGGGGCUGACCCCUGCCUUUGAUUGUCAUUCUCCUGGGAAGCCCAGUCUCAGUCCCUCCCCCAACACUGUCCACACUGCCCCUCCCCACUGUUUAUUUAUUGCACGGAUCUAAGUUAUUCUCCCCAGCCAGAGCCCGAGCUCCUGCUCCCUGGGAAAAGUGGCGUAUGGCCCUGAGCUGGGCUUUAUAUUUUAUAUCUGCAAAUAAAUCACAUUUUAUCUUAUAUUUAGGGAAAGCCGGAGAGCAACAACAAAAAAUGUUUAAGCCGGGCGCGGUGGCUCACAUCUGUAAUCCCAGCACUUUGGGAGUCCAAGGAGGGGGAUCGCUUGAGUCCAGGAGUUUGAGACCAGCCUGGACAACAUGGUGAAACCCCAUCUCUACAAAAAAUACAAAAAUUAGCCAUGCAUGGUGGCUCAUGCCUGUAGUCCCAGCUACUUGGGAGGCUGAGGCAGGAGGAUCACUUAAGCCCAGAAGGCAGAGGUUGUAGUGAGCUGAGAUCGCACCACUGCACUCCAGCCUGGGCAACAUAGCAAAAUCCUGUCUCAAAAAAAAAGUUAAAAAAUAUUGCCCGGCUCCUAGAAUUUAUUUAUUUCCUGACUUACAGCAAGCGAGUUAUCGUCUUCUGUAUUUUGUAGACUUUCUAAAUAAAGUCAAAUUCUUUCUUUUUCCACAGAGAA